AGGCUGCCCGGGCCGUGGCAGGAAGCCGGAAGCAGCCGCGGCCCCAGUUCGGGAGACAUGGCGGGCGUUAAAGAGAAGAAACCAGUGUGUGUGUAGUAUGUGUUUUUUGCAUGGGGCAGUUGGUAAAAACACCGCGUCCCUUAUCUGUAUGGCUUCAGAGCAAUGCGAGACGGAAAAGGUUUUUUGCAAGGCUUCCUGUAUUUUGCUCUCGUGGCAUUAUCCUUCAGUGGGGCUAUUGGACUGACUUUUCUUAUGCUGGGAUGUGCCUUAGAGGAUUAUGGCGUUUACUGGCCCUUAUUCGUCCUGAUUUUCCACGCCAUCUCCCCCAUCCCCCAUUUCAUUGCCAAAAGAGUCACCUAUGACUCAGAUGCAACCAGUAGUGCCUGUCGGGAACUGGCAUAUUUCUUCACUACUGGAAUUGUUGUUUCUGCCUUUGGAUUUCCUGUUAUUCUUGCUCGUGUGGCUGUGAUCAAAUGGGGAGCCUGCGGCCUUGUGUUGGCAGGCAAUGCAGUCAUUUUCCUUACAAUUCAAGGGUUUUUCCUUAUAUUUGGAAGAGGAGAUGAUUUUAGCUGGGAGCAGUGGUAGCACUUUAUUCUGAUUACAGUGCAUUGAAUUUCUUAGAACUCAUACUAUCUGUAUACAUGUGCACAUGCGGCAUUUUACUAUGAAAUUUAAUAUGCUGGGUUUUUUAAUACCUUUAUAUAUCAUGUUCACUUUAAGAAAGACUUCAUAAGUAGGAGAUGAGUUUUAUUCUCAGCAAAUAGACCUGUCAAAUUUAGAUUAUGUUACUCAAAUUAUGUUACUUGUUUGGCUGUUCAUGUAGUCACGGUGCUCUCAGAAAAUAUAUUAACGCAGUCUUGUAGGCAGCUGCCACCUUAUGCAGUGCAUCGAAACCUUUUGCUUGGGGAUGUGCUUGGAGAGGCAGAUAACGCUGAAGCAGGCCUCUCAUGACCCAGGAAGGCCGGGGUGGAUCCCUCUUUGUGUUGUAGUCCAUGCUAUUAAAAGUGUGGCCCACAGACCAAGAGCCUCAACAUUUCCUAGAGCCUUAUUAGAAAUGCAGAAUCUGAAGCCCCACUCUGGACCCAGGACAUUUUGAUGAGAUCCAAAGGAGUUGUAUGCACAUGAAAGUUUGAGAAGCAUCAUCAUAGAGAAGUAAACAUCACACCCAACUUCCUUAUCUUUCCAGUGGCUAAACCACUUAACCUCUCUGGGUGUUACCUGCUCAUUUGUUUAAAAAAAAAAAAAAAGUCUCACCUGCUUUCAUGCUGAGGACAAGUUCAGAUGUUCAAGCCUAUAAUAUUUAGGCAGUUCCUCAAAUUUAUGAAAAGUGUUCUCAGAAUUGGGAGACAGUCAAAGGGUACAAAGCCUCAGUUAGGAGGAAUAAGUGUGAUUUUUUUUUAAAGAUCACUUGCACAGCAUGCUAAAUAUAGGAAUAAUUGAAUGUAUAUUUCAAUAUUGCUAAGAGAGUAAAUUUCUAAUGUUCUCAUAAAAAAGUUAAAUAUUUGAGAUCAUAUGUUAAUUAGUGUAAUCAUUCCACCUUAUAUUCAAAAAUCAUAAAACCGUAUUGUACCCUAUAAAAAUAUACAAUAAUUUGUCAAUAUAUAAUCAAAAUAAAAAACAAAACAUACUCUCUCCCCCAAAAAAACAUCUCAGUGGGGAACAGAUGUAUCUUUUCAUCUGAAAGACAAUGCUGGGGGAAGAGCUCCACUGAGAUGCGGGCAGGGAGGCUGGGCUCGAGCCAGCCCCUGCGUUAGCAGGAGGGGGAGAACAGAUAGGUAACUCUUUUACAUUUCCUUUAUGAUCUGGCACUUCUCCCCAGCUCCUUCCCUCUGCCCCCCACCCCUACUCCUCAACAGUUCUGGUUUGCCCUGACUUCUCUACGGCUCUGGCUUCUUCCCGAAGAGAUAUAGGAGCCAUGUAAGCACGCAGUGGGUGAACUGCUUAAUUUCACUACGUGUUGAUGUACUUGUCUUCCGUCCUGUAGGUCUUUUCUAUAUAACUUUAUGCCACCCUUAAAUGAAUCAUUGGGUAUACCUGUCAUGUUGGAUCCUGUAAUCACAGUUUUCCCUGCUCACCUUUUUGUCUAAGAUCUAUUGAGAAAGGGAAAUAUGGGAAGGAGAACCAUUUGAUCAGAAUACAACCAAUAGUCUUUAAGCAUUGUUAAAGUAUGAAACUGAAAUACAUUCAAAACACUUAAUCCUUGAGGCUUGUGAUCUGAGUAAUUAGCAGGUAUGAUGCUGGGACUGGAAAAUAGAAAGUAAUAACUAAAGGGUUAAUGUGCAACGUUAUUUUUUGGCCUUGUUCAUGAUUUUAUGUUUUCAGUGUCCUGUGUACAUAUAGAAUUGUUAAAGUUGUCAUUUCCAAUAUUUAUAUUAGAAAAAUUAUUUAGAUACUUUAUAAUUUUAACCGGCAUUUUUAAUAAUGACACUUGCAUUUAUUGUAUUGUAAUAAAUUUCACUUUUAACUUUAAAAGUUUAACUUUAAAAUUUUUUUGUGAUGUUGCCUUGCCUGAAAAGAUAACAAAAAUGAGAGAAUUUCUUGAUGUUUUAAAAUGGGCAGUUUUGAGCAAUAAUCUGUCCUAACAGAACAGUAGCAAUAAGUUUUAGGAUACCAUCUUGAAUGUCUAGUUGGUGUGCAAUAGCUUUUCUUUCUAAGAUGGCAAUAAUGAUUCAUUUCUACUACAUUUUGCAAAAGUGUUUUUGUUGCUUAUACACAUUUUCAAUAACCAAGGUAGCCUUCAUAUGUAGCCUUAAAGCAUUACCUCUUGAUUGUAUCUUUAGAUUGAUAUAAAGUACUUGCAUAUAGAGUAUUUGAAGUGAUAGAUUAUUAGAUUUGCUCUAUGUCUGAAAAGAGAGCUAUUCUGCAGUGCCUAAAUAUCAUUUAAACAGUAAAUAUUAAUAGGAAAUAUUGCUAUAUCUGAAUAUAUAAUACAAAAGUUUGAUCAUGGUGACACAAAUGUUGGACAUUUUUUUCCUUAUAAAAGGCUCUUUUUUUAUAUAUUGUACAAUAUAUUUGGAGAUUCAGAGCAUAGUGACUAUAGUCGAAAACUGAGAUUGCACUUCCAAAAUUGGCCACAAGUAAAUAAUCUUAUGAAGGGAUUCUUUAUCAUGUUUCAAACAAGUGGGUUACAAGCAGACUUUGAGACACUUUUCCACAGAAACAAUACUAUGAAUUGGUGAUUGAGUUCCCAGGCCAAGCCUCCCUCAACAGGUUCAACUCUAAUAUACCUAACCUGUGAUACUGAAGGUGCCUGCCUGAGUUUUGGGUCUCUGAGACAGGGUAGUGUGAGUAGUUUGGAGGAAGGACAGUGCAACUUUCCACCCCUUUUCCUAAGAACAAGGUCUUUCUCCUUUUAAUUUUUCCACUCAUUUUCACCUCCUAAUGCCCUUGAGAUCCAGGUACACUCCUGGGAGUUUUGUUCACCUCUCCCAACUGAGAACCUUCCCACUGGGCUCCAUCCUCCCUCCUGAGGUUCUUCAUAUUCCAGAGUCACCCACCCUUCUCCUCCCAUUAGUCAGUUCUCUAAGUACAGCUGAUGUCAUGUGGUGCUGAGAAGAAAGCAGAUCACACUUCAUCACAGAAAGAAUGCCUUGUGAUUAUCUUCUCCACAUCUGAAAUUCCUUUUGACACCUGCAUUGGGCCGACUGCCAUUCCCAUGACUGCUGCACCUGCGUUUUUAGAGAAUGCCUCAUAACCCACUGAUUCUCAUUCACAGAGAAUGGGAGAACGGAAUGAAGAAAGAUUCCAGCAGCUUAUAGAAGGAUAGCAAUAUUUUGGGACAGGGAAAAUCCUGUCAUACCUCAUCUCUUCCUCAGGAGGAGUUCUGAGCUGGUCCUGCUUUUCAUAGUUGUUUCUUUUCUUCCACUUAAGAACUCAUAGAUUUUUCUUACUGUCCUAAGGAAGUCCUUACCUCUGAGGUAUCUCCUCAAUGAAUACUGUUUUCAAGGCUGAAAUAGUUCAUUAUGUUAAUAACCUUCUUUAUGUUCUCAGGGAAAUGCUUAGGUGGUGUCACAAAAUGUGCCUUUUCUUUUCUUUUUUUUUUUUUUUUUUUGAGGCAGAGUCUCGCUCUGUUGCCCAGGCUGGAGUGCAGUGGUGCGAUCUUGGCUCACUGCAAGCUCCGCCUCCCGGGUUCACGCCAUUCUCCUGCCUCAGCCUCCCAAGGAGCUGGGACUACAGGCUCCCGCCACCACGCCUGGCUAAUUUUUUUGUAUUUUUAGUAAAGACGGGUUUCAUCGUGUUAGCCAGGAUGGUCUCGAUCUCCUGACCUCAUGAUCCGCCCGCCUCUGCCUCCCAAAGUGCUGGGAUUACAGGCCUGAGCCACUGUGCCCAGCCAAAAUGUGCCUUUGCAAAGUUUGCGAAAUCAGAUUUUGUAUCCCAAUAGAACCAAAAUAUUUAUGAGGAUGCUAGCAUUUUCCAAGCAUAGUAAUUAGUUCACAACUGAGAAAUAUUAUGUCUGUAGUAGAUAAAUAUUAGUUGUGCAUUUUAAUUUAAUUCUCCUUUUUCCAUUUUGUCUCAUGAAGUACCUUAUUGCAAAAAUCCCACUGAGUAAUAGCUCAUAAAUUAUAAUCUUUCAAAUAGCCAUGCUACCAGCGUACAACAGUGAUACAUGUAACCCCAAAUGUGAUGUGAGAGGACGAUUACUUUGUAAAUAAAACUUGUUAUUGACAUUUUAA